ACUCUGGGCAGGAUCCAACGUCGCUCCAGCUGCUCUUGACGACUCCACAGAUACCCCGAAGCCAUGGCAAGCAAGGGCUUGCAGGACCUGAAGCAACAGGUGGAGGGGACCGCCCAGGAAGCCGUGUCAGCGGCCGGAGCGGCAGCUCAGCAAGUGGUGGACCAGGCCACAGAGGCGGGGCAGAAAGCCAUGGACCAGCUGGCCAAGACCACCCAGGAAACCAUCGACAAGACUGCUAACCAGGCCUCUGACACCUUCUCUGGGAUUGGGAAAAAAUUCGGCCUCCUGAAAUGACAGCAGGGAGACUUGGGUCGGCCUCCUGAAAUGACAGCAGGGAGACUUGGGUGACCCCCCUUCCAGGCGCCAUCUAGCACAGCCUGGCCCUGAUCUCCGGGCAGCCACCACCUCCUCGGUCUGCCCCCUCAUUAAAAUUCACGUUCCCACCCUGUGUCCACUUCAUGAUUCCUCGCAAGCUGGGCCCAGUCCUCUCAUCCCAAGAGCAGAGCCACCGUAGCCGGAGUCCUAGCCUCCCAAAUUCGGAAAUCCAAUCCAACGGUCUCAGGAAUGUUUUCCAUCCCGCCACGCGCCUCCCGAAGCUCCCAGACCGGAGGCUCAGCCCCCAUCUCG